AGUCACUGUCUCCCCGCCCCACGGUUCCGAGUAAGGACCGGAGCUCCACUCCGGGGGUGGAGCGCGGGCUCCCCGCAGGGAAAGGUGCGCAGCGUUCCCGACCCCAAAACGAGCGGCGCUUGGGAGCGUGCGUGCCUCCCCGAGAGCCCCGGGCGCCACCCGUGGGCUGGACGAGGUGGGCGCUGGGGCGUGGGGCCGGCGGCGCAGAGAAGCCACGGCCACCUGCCGCCUCCCCUGCACCUGGCGGAGCAUCCCUCACUCUACAGUCCCUGGAGGCGGCGCCGGAAACCUGGCGGCCGGGACCGCGAUUCUGGAAGCCCCGGAGCUCGCCCGGCCGGAGGAGCCGGGGCGCGGUUCCGGCGAGAUUGGCGACUUGCUUCCUUUUGCAGAACGGCCGCUCCUCUCUCGGUCCAGCUGCGACGCUGGGAAAGCGCCAGACUUGGUCUGUCACGGGAGCCCCCGCGGGGCGUGGCGAGGGAGAGCUGGCCUAGGCUGCGAGGGACUCUCGUUUCUUGCCUGGAGAGCCAGGAAGAGGGCGAGGGCAGAGCAUCCUUGGGCGGAGAUGCCUUUAAAAAAUCAUCCACCGCAGCGGUAGAAACAGUUUUGUUUGGCUUUAUUUAUACGGAAUGGUUUUUCAGUGAAAUGCUGUCUUGCUUAAAAGAAGAGAUGCCUCCCCAGGAGCUCACCCGGCGACUGGCCACAGUGAUCACUCAUGUCGAUGAAAUUAUGCAGCAGGAAGUCAGACCCCUGAUGGCGGUGGAGAUAAUAGAACAACUUCACAGACAAUUUGCCAUUCUUUCAGGAGGCCGAGGGGAGGAUGGCGCCCCCAUCAUCACGUUCCCAGAGUUUUCGGGGUUCAAACACAUCCCAGAUGAAGACUUCCUGAAUGUCAUGACCUACCUGACUAGCAUCCCCAGUGUGGAGGCUGCCAGCAUUGGAUUCAUUGUUGUUAUCGACAGACGAAGAGACAAGUGGAGCUCCGUAAAGGCAUCCUUGACACGAAUAGCUGUGGCAUUUCCAGGAAACUUACAGCUCAUAUUCAUCCUUCGUCCAUCUCGCUUUAUCCAGAGGACAUUCACUGACAUUGGCAUUAAAUACUAUCGAAAUGAGUUUAAAACGAAAGUGCCGAUCAUCAUGGUAAACUCUGUCUCUGACCUUCACGGCUACAUCGACAAAAGCCAACUGACCCGGGAAUUAGGGGGGACUUUGGAAUAUCGCCACGGUCAGUGGGUAAAUCACCGCACUGCCAUCGAAAACUUUGCCUUGACCUUGAAGACCACUGCCCAGAUGCUGCAGACGUUUGGGUCCUGCCUGGCCACAGCAGAGCUGCCCAGAAGCAUGCUAUCCACGGAAGACCUUCUCAUGUCCCACACAAGGCAGCGGGACAAGCUGCAGGAUGAGCUGAAAUUACUUGGAAAGCAGGGGACCACAUUGCUGUCAUGCAUCCAAGAACCAGCAACCAAAUGUCCCAACAGCAAACUCAAUCUCAACCAACUUGAGAAUGUAACUACCAUGGAAAGGUUAUUAGUUCAACUGGAUGAAACAGAAAAAGCCUUUAGUCACUUUUGGUCUGAGCAUCAUCUGAAGCUUAACCAGUGCCUACAACUACAGCAUUUUGAGCACGAUUUUUGUAAGGCUAAGCUUGCCCUGGAUAAUUUGCUGGAAGAGCAAGCAGAGUUUACAGGCAUUGGAGACAGCGUGAUGCACGUGGAGCAGAUUCUUAAGGAACACAAAAAACUGGAGGAAAAAAGCCAGGAGCCCCUGGAAAAGGCCCAGCUGCUGGCACUGGUUGGGGACCAGCUCAUCCAAAGCCACCAUUAUGCAGCAGAUGCCAUCAGGCCCCGGUGUGUGGAGCUCAGGCACCUCUGUGACGAUUUCAUCAAUGGAAACAAGAAAAAAUGGGACAUUUUAGGAAAGUCCUUAGAGUUUCAUAGACAGCUGGACAAGGUCAGCCAAUGGUGUGAGGCAGGAAUCUACCUCUUGGCUUCCCAAGCUGUAGACAAGUGCCAGUCUCGAGAAGGGGUUGAUAUCGCCUUGAACGACAUUGCGACAUUCCUGGGCACAGUCAAGGAGUACCCGUUGCUCAGCCCCAAGGAGUUUUACAACGAGUUUGAGUUGCUGCUCACCCUCGAUGCAAAGGCCAAAGCCCAGAAAGUUUUGCAGAGGCUGGAUGAUGUCCAGGAAAUAUUUCACAAGAGGCAAGUGAGUCUGAUGAAACUGGCAGCCAAACAGACUCGUCCAGUGCAACCUGUGGCCCCACAUCCUGAGUCUUCACCAAAAUGGGUGUCAUCAAAAACCAGCCAGCCCUCCACCUCGGUCCCUCUAGCUCGUCCUCUGAGAACGUCUGAGGAACCUUAUACGGAGACAGAGUUGAACUCCCGGGGAAAGGAAGAUGAUGAGACUAAAUUUGAAGUCAAGAGUGAAGAAAUCUUUGAAAGCCAUCAUGAAAGGGGGAACCCUGAGCUGGAGCAGCAGGCCAGGCUCGGAGACCUUUCCCCCCGCAGGCCAGGUGUGGUGGCUCAGGUCUGUAAUCCCAACACUUUCCAACACUUUGGGAGGCUGAGGUAGGAGGAUUGCUCGAGCCCAGGAGUUGAAGACCAGCCUGAGCAACAUAGUGAAGACACCAUCUCCACAAGAAAUUAAAACAUUUAGCGGGAUGUGGUGGGGUGCACCUGUAGUCUCAGUUACUCAGGAGACUGAGGUGAGAAGAUUGCUUGAGCCCAGGAAGCUAAGUCUGCAGUGAGCUAAGCUGUGAUCACACAGCUGCACUGCAGCCUGGGUGACAGAGCAAAACCCUGUCUCAAAGAGGAAGAAAAAAAACAAAAAACGUAUGGCAGACUGCCAAAUCAUACUUAUGAGAAACACAAAGGAAUAAAGUUACAGCACUCAACUAAAGAAACAAAAAUAUCUUUAUGUUCUUGCAAAAGAACUUUGAGAAAAGGCAAAAUUAGCCACUGAGUUAAUCAAGAGGUAGAAUCUGUAAGACUACUGUUUUUGUUCUACCACCAGCUUUGACUAAAUACCUUAAGAUCACCAGUCUUUGCUGCAACUGUUUAAUCUGUAUUUCCUUAUUCCUUUUUGAUUUUAUAGAUUUGAGUUUUGCUGCAUAACUAAACAAAUUUGCUUGGUAUAUAGAAGGCUUUCAGAUUUUGGGGAGAUGAUUAAUUAUUCAGAACCCUAAGUGGACACUGUACAAGGCAUGGUUGCCUUCAGAACUUACAGCUCGUAAAAAAACACAUGGAAUGAUUAGUAGGUAGUACGAUAAUAUAUGUGACUAAAUAUAAAUUUGGGGAGAAGGGAAGGAAGAGAUGCUUAAGGGAAGAGAGGAGGUAGAAUUGGAUUUCCAAAAUUUCAACAGGUAUAGGAAAAACAGUGCUCUUGGCAAGGGAAACCAACUUAAGCAAGGUAUGGUCAUGAUUGACAUUUGUGAUAGAUAAUAGUGGCAGUGAUAAAAAAAAAAAAACCAAGCUAUAGGGAAUGAAGGAGGAAAAGUUUACGUAGGGCGUUGAAAACCAGGUAGAAGAGUUUAGAUUUGAUGCUGGAGGCAGUGAGGAGUCUUUGAGGUCUGGAGUAAAGGAAUAUUGUAAUGAAAGCUAUGAUUAAGGAUUGUGUCACUGCAGAAUGCGGAAGUGAUCGGAAGGAAAACUGACUCAAAGAGACAUCGAAUAUUCCUCUCAUUAUUAUCACAGAAUGAAUAACCUUGCAUAUCAAGAGUUCUCUGGUUCUAUUCUCAUUGCAGCUAUAGCAUCCAAUUAAAGUCCCCAAAUAUAGGUCAUUAAUUAAUUCUUCCAAGUCAUCACAUUUUAGUACCAACUACAAACACUCCUACCACGACUUGCAAGUAAAAAGUUCUACCAUAAACAAAUAAUUCGGAUGCUUACAAGUUUUAAAUAUAGAUUGAGUUACACAAUAUGCCAUGUGAAGAACUGAGCAGGAAUCAGGUAAAAACAGAUGAGAGCACAUUACAUGCAACUAUAUCGAAGCACCAGACACUCCAAAGUAGGUGUAAGGGCAUUCCUGAUAUUAAGAGAUUAGGGUUAAAAUUGACUGUAUUUCAGACAGCUAACCGUGUCAAAGAAAAGGAAAACGUAACCUUUUCAAAUGGUAUCUUAAAGCGCUAUAACUACAGGUGAUUUCAUCCCUCUCUCAACAGAUUAUAGUCAUGCAUUGCUUAACAAUGAGGAUAAGUUCUGAGAAAUGCAUUUUUUUUUUUUUUGAGACAGUCUCGCUCUGUCGUCCAGGUUGGAGAGCAGUGGCACAAUCUCAGGUCAUUGCAACCUCCCUUUCCCAGGUUCAAGCAAUUCUCCUGCCUCAGCCUCCCGAGUAGUUGGGAUUACUGGUGUGUGCCACCACACCUGGCUGAUUUUUGUAUUUUUAGUAGAGAUGGGGUUUCACCAUGUUGGCCAGGCUGGUCUCAAACUCCUAACCUCAGGUGGUCCACUUGCCUCGGCCUCCCAAAGUGCUGGGAUUACAGGCGUGAGCCAUGGCGCCUGGCCAAUAAAUGCAUCUUUAGGUGACCACAUCGAUGUGCAAACAUCCCAGGUUAUACAUACGAGAACCUAGAUGGAAUAGCCUACUAGACACCUAGAUAUAUGGUAGAGCCUAUUGCUCCUGGGCUAGAAACCUGUACAGCAUGUUGCUGUACUGAAUACUGCAGGCAAUUGUAAGACAAUGGAAAGUAUUUGUGUAUCUAAACACAUCUAAAUAUACAAAAGGUACAGUAAAAAUCUGAAAUAAAAGAUAAAAAAUGGUACACCUGUAUAGGGCAGUUCCAUUACAAUUUCAUGGGACUAUCAUCAUAUAUGUGAUCCAUCGUUAACCGAAACGUCAUUUUGUGGCACAUGACUACAUUAGGAAAGAACAUCUCCCCAUCCAGAUAUUCCAGCAUGAGUCAUUUAACAAAAAGUACAUCUUAGGUGGCUCUAUAAUGCAGAGAACAUGAUAAUCCUAUAGGAACAGGGCUAAGACCAUGUAGUACAUUAAGACAGAAGGAAUGAUUAUAUAAGCAAUGUUCAUGAAAAAGUUUAAAUACACAUCUCAUGAUAAUUUUUCAGUUGUUUAUUGGAAACUAUAGAUUUUUUUUAAACUCACUAAUUAUUUUGCCAUACAAGAGCAAAAUUCAAGUAAUACAAAUAUUUAACAUUUUGGUAUAAAAUUAACAAUAUGGAAAAAAGAUGCAAACCAACCAAAAGGUAAAAAAAUUUUAACAAUAACACUGUGUAUAACCAUCUUCUAUUCAAGUGACCAUCCAAGCUGAUAGUUUAUUUUCCCUUUGUUGACAUUUUUUAAAAAGAUAGCCCUACACUGGAGCACCAAAAAGUUUUUUCCUUCUUUUUUAAAAGGUUGGAACCCUUUUAUUUACAGAUACUCUUCUCAGUACUUUAAGUAAGUGUGAUGAAGGAAUCAUCUAGCAACUUCCUUCUUAGAAAAAAAGGAAGUGCCUUCAUAUUUCCUUGAAAUUUAAACUUGUUCCAUUCUAUUCUAAGCAAAAAUUAAAAGGACACAGUUCAGAAGAGCUCUUUCAGCAAAUAAAUAAUUGUUUCACAAAAGCACUGCUGUAAACAAGAUCACUUUGAUGGCCAGAGACACUUAUGUUUUCAACCAAUGGCAACCUUAAACACUUCCAAGUAUAGAUACACAGGGUAUAUAUGGGCAAAAGGCAAUACAUCAUUAAUCAAUCAACUAAUAAAAAUUAAUUAUAAGCUUGUUGCUUGGUCAAAUAUGCUUUUGUUCUCUAUGUUUUUUUAAUUGGUCAGAAAACUUAAACUGUAAUGAUCUAAAACCCUGUAUCUACUCUGAAAGUAACUACAACCUAGAAUGUUUGACACUGUAGUUUUGACAUUAGUUAAAAAUUCUAAAUUAUCUAAGCAAUGUAAACAAGCCUCAAAUUUCAAAAUAGAAAAAAAUUAAAAUUUCUGUAAACAUUAAAAAGCUACCUGCUAAAAA